AUGGGCCUCCUGGCAGGCGUGAGCCAGCAGGCCUCUGGGAAAAUCAAGGGCAGGCAGAGGAAGCCUGGGGCCCACUGUGGAGACGUCUGCCCACCGGCUGUUCCCAUCUUCGUCUUCCCACUGGACCCAGAGCCGGUCCUGUUGGUGGGCGGGGCCCUGUUGGUGGGCGAGGCCCUGUUGGUGGCUUGGGUCCUGUUGGUGGGCGGGGCCCUGUUGGUGGGCGGGGCCCUGUUGGUGGCUUGGGUCCUGUUGGUGGGCGGGGCCCUGUUGGUGGGCGGGGCCCUGUUGGUGGCUUGGGUCCUGUUGGUGGGCGGGGCCCUGUUGGUGGCUUGGGUCCUGUUGGUGGGCGGGGCCCUGUUGGUGGCUUGGGUCCUGUUGGUGGGCGGGGCCCUGUUGGUGGGCGGGGCCCUGUUGGUGGCUUGGGUCCUGUUGGUGGGCGGGGUCCUGUUGGUGGGCGGGGCCCUGUUGGUAACCCCUGGGGGUGGAGAUGGAGGCACUCAUUCAACCCCAGAUGUGAUUCAGGCACUCAGGCCCCUGGACAGCUCCGGGCUGGUCCCAGACACUCUUGGGGGCAAAAAAAGAGGAAGCUCACGUUUCCAGCCUCCUGUGCAUCCCAUCCUAAGAACCCCUGGAGUGUGGCUCCGCGGAGCAAGAAAGGCUUUCGGCCAGGACCAAGGAGAGGGCCUGUGGAUAGGUCAGUCACCCCCAAUGCUACUUCCCAUUCUCCAGUCAGGCCCGCUGAGGGUGACCCACUCUCCCUUCUUCCCACAAGGACCACAUUCUAGCCAACGGGACGUGAGUGGAGUUGAAGUGUUCCACUGGUGAACGACUCCCUUAAAAGGAAUGGGCAUGCAUGCCC